AGAGGAAGCCUCGCUCUCUCACCCAGGCUGGAGUGCAGUGGCAGGAACUUGGCUCACUGCAACCUCCGCUUCCCAGGUUCAAGUGAUUCUCCUGCCUCAGCCUCCAGAGUAGCUGGGAUUACAGGCGCACGUCACCACACCUGGCUAAUUUUUGUAUUUUUAGUAGAGACGGGGUUUCUCCAUGUUGGUCAGGCUGGUCUCGAACUCCUGACCUCGUGAUCCGCCCGCCUCGGCCUCCCAAAGUGCUGGGAUUACAGGCGUGAGCCACCGUGCCCGGCCGGGAGGUCACUUUAAGGAGGGCUGUCCAACUGCAAGGAGCCGCAAGCAGGAAGUGAAACCACAGCACUUCAAAAAAAGAGGGAGACUGGGACAAGCGUAUCUAAGAGGCUGAACAUGAAUCCACAGAUCAGAAAUCCGAUGGAGCGGAUGUAUCGAGACACAUUCUACGACAACUUUGAAAACGAACCCAUCCUCUAUGGUCGGAGCUACACUUGGCUGUGCUAUGAAGUGAAAAUAAAGAGGGGCCGCUCAAAUCUCCUUUGGGACACAGGGGUCUUUCGAGGCCCGGUACUACCCAAACGUCAGUCGAAUCACAGGCAGGAGGUGUAUUUCCGGUUUGAGAACCACGCAGAAAUGUGCUUCUUAUCUUGGUUCUGUGGCAACCGACUGCCUGCUAACAGGCGCUUCCAGAUCACCUGGUUUGUAUCAUGGAACCCCUGCCUGCCCUGUGUGGUGAAGGUGACCAAAUUCUUGGCUGAGCACCCCAAUGUCACCCUGACCAUCUCUGCCGCCCGCCUCUACUACUACCGGGAUAGAGAUUGGCGGUGGGUGCUCCUCAGGCUGCAUAAGGCAGGGGCCCGUGUGAAGAUCAUGGACUAUGAAGGUGAGAGGUGCAGGGGUCAGGGGAGCAUGACGGGGAGGAACAGCCUCAGAGAUGGAUGGAUCUGCAAUGCCAUGGCUGGGGGUGUUCCAGGGCAGCCUGCAGGGGUGGGGCUGGCACUGAUUGCAACUGACAGCCAGGAGACCAGGCCUGGGAGGGCAGGCCCAGGGUCAGGGGAGAGCCUGAGUGCUUCCCACCUCUUCAUCUCAGACUUUGCAUACUGCUGGGAAAACUUUGUGUGCAAUGAAGGUCAGCCAUUCAUGCCUUGGUACAAAUUCGAUGACAAUUAUGCAUCCCUGCACCGCACGCUAAAGGAGAUUCUCAGAAACCCGAUGGAGGCAAUGUACCCACACAUAUUCUACUUCCACUUUAAAAACCUACUGAAAGCCUGUGGUCGGAACGAAAGCUGGCUGUGCUUCACCAUGGAAGUUACAAAGCACCACUCAGCUGUCUUCCGGAAGAGGGGCGUCUUCCGAAACCAGGUGGAUCCUGAGACCCAUUGUCAUGCAGAAAGGUGCUUCCUCUCUUGGUUCUGUGACGACAUACUGUCUCCUAACACAAACUACGAGGUCACCUGGUACACAUCUUGGAGCCCUUGCCCAGAGUGUGCAGGGGAGGUGGCCGAGUUCCUGGCCAGGCACAGCAACGUGAAUCUCACCAUCUUCACCGCCCGCCUCUGCUACUUCUGGGAUACAGAUUACCAGGAGGGGCUCUGCAGCCUGAGUCAGGAAGGGGCCUCCGUGAAGAUCAUGGGCUACAAAGAUUUUGUAUCUUGUUGGAAAAACUUUGUGUACAGUGAUGAUGAGCCAUUCAAGCCUUGGAAGGGACUACAAACCAACUUUCGACUUCUGAAAAGAAGGCUACGGGAGAUUCUCCAGUGAGGGGUCUCCCUGGGCCUCAUGGUCUGUCUCUUCUAGCCUCCUGCUCAUGCUGCACGGGCCUCCCCUCCAUCCUGCACCAGCUGUGCUUUUGCCUGGUCAUCCUGAGCCCCUCCUGGCCUCAGGGCCAUUCCAUAGUGCCCCCCUGCCUCACCACCUCCUCCCCGCUCUCCCAGGCUCUUCUUGUAGAGGCUCUCCAUCCACCUCCCCAGUCCUGUUCCCCCAGCCUGGGUGCCCCUAACUUGACUCUUCCCAUCUCCCCAGCAUAACCAAAUCUUUUUUUUUUUUUUUUUUUUUUGAGACGGAGUUUCACUCUGUCGCCCAGACUAGAGUGCAAUGGCUGGAUCUCAGCUCACUGCAAACUCUGCUUACUGGGUUCAAGUGAUUCUCCUGUCUCAGCUUCUGAGUAGCUGGGAUUACAGAUGCCUGCCACCACGCCCAGCUAAUUUUUUUUUUUUUUUUUUUUUUUUUUUGUAUUUUUAGUAGUGACUGGGUUUCACCAUGUUGGCCAGGCUGGUCUUGAACUCCUGACCUCAGGUGAUCUGCCCAUCUCUGUCUCCCAAAGUGCUGGGAUUACGGGCGUGAGCCACCCGGCUCGGCCGCACAACCAAAUCUUAUUAAACUCAAUCUAGUCUGGCCCUGGUGACUCACGCCUUUCGGAGGCAGAGGUGGGAGAAUCGCUUGAGCCCAGAAGUUUGAGACCAGCCUGGGCCACACGACAAAGCCCCAUUUCUACAAAAAAAAAUACCAAAAAAAAGCCAGAUGUGGUGGCAUGCACCUGUAGUUUAAGCUACUUGGGAGGAUGAAGUGGGAGGACUGCUUGAGCCGGGGAGGUGGAGGCUGGAGUAAACUGAGAUCGCGCCACAGAACUCCAGUUUGAGCAACAGAUCAAGACCCUGCCUGAAAAUAAAUCAAUAAAUACACUCAACCUAAAUGGAUAUGAAUAUAUGUAAGUUGAAAACCA